GUUAAGUGCUGCCUCUGCAUAACAUGCAGGUGGAAGUCCCAUGGUCUUUCCUCAGGUUCACUUCAAUUCUCUUCUUGGAAUUCUCAGGAAUUCCGUGUAUUAUUUUGAUUUGUCUGAAUCACAUGAUUGCUCAGAAGCAGACAGCACCAGCAAGCCAGCACUCAACCCUAAGAGCAGCCUUCAGUGAGCAGUCUGCUGAAAUUCUAAAACAGAGGAAAACCAGCAUACACAUGAAACUACUGUUCUUUGAGAUCAACUUAUCUCAGACAGAAUGAUUGACCAGCUCCAAGGAACAUGGAAGUCCAUUUCUUGUGAAAAUUCCGAAGACUACAUGAAGGAGCUGGGUAUAGGAAGAGCCAGCAGGAAACUGGGCCGUUUGGCAAAACCCACUGUGACCAUCAGUACAGAUGGAGAUGUCAUCACAAUAAAAACCAAAAGCAUCUUUAAAAAUAAUGAGAUCUCCUUUAAGCUGGGAGAAGAGUUUGAGGAAAUCACGCCAGGUGGCCACAAAACAAAGAGUAAAGUAACCUUAGAUAAGGAGUCCCUGAUUCAAGUUCAGGACUGGGAUGGCAAAGAAACCACCAUAACGAGAAAGCUGGUGGAUGGGAAAAUGGUGGUGGAAAGUACUGUGAACAGUGUUAUCUGUACACGAACAUACGAGAAAGUAUCAUCAAACUCAGUCUCAAACUCUUAAGGCUUUCUCAAGCUGUCAUCCAAACUACUGAGGUUGUUUAAAUAAAACUCCAAAGUAAAAUAUUA